GUGGCCCCGUCUGGCUAGUCCUGUCUAGCGCGCCCAUUUCGAGCCCAAGUUUCCAGCUCGGGUUUCCGGGCUCAGAAUUUUCCAGGAGUGGGUUCUUGGGCAGUGGCUGUGGGAGCAGGAAUGGCGCAGCUAGAGGGUUACUGUUUCUCGGCCGCCUUGAGCUGUACCUUUUUAGUGUCCUGCCUCCUCUUCUCCGCCUUCAGCCGGGCGCUGCGAGAGCCCUACAUGGACGAGAUCUUCCACCUGCCUCAGGCGCAGCGCUACUGUGAGGGCCAUUUCUCCCUUUCCCAGUGGGAUCCCAUGAUUACUACAUUACCUGGCUUGUACCUGGUGUCAGUUGGAGUGGUCAAACCUGCCAUUUGGAUCUUUGCAUGGUCUGAACAUGUUGUCUGCUCCAUUGGGAUGCUCAGAUUUGUUAAUCUUCUCUUCAGUGUUGGCAACUUCUAUUUACUAUAUUUGCUUUUCCACAAGGUACAACCCAGAAACAAGGCUGCCUCAAGUAUCCAGAGAGUCUUGUCAACAUUAACACUAGCAGUAUUUCCAACACUUUAUUUUUUUAACUUCCUUUAUUAUACAGAAGCAGGAUCUAUGUUUUUUACUCUUUUUGCAUAUUUGAUGUGUCUUUAUGGAAAUCAUAAAACUUCAGCCUUCCUUGGAUUUUGUGGCUUCAUGUUUCGGCAAACAAAUAUCAUCUGGGCUGUCUUCUGUGCAGGGAAUGUCAUUGCACAAAAGUUAACUGAGGCUUGGAAAACUGAGCUACAAAAGAAGGAAGACAGACUUCCACCUAUUAAAGGACCAUUUGCAGAAUUCAGAAAAAUUCUUCAGUUUCUUUUGGCUUAUUCCAUGUCCUUUAAAAACUUGAGUAUGCUUUUCUGUUUGACUUGGCCCUACAUCCUUCUGGGAUUUCUGUUUUGUGCUUUUGUAGUAGUUAAUGGUGGAAUUGUUAUUGGCGAUCGGAGUAGUCAUGAAGCCUGUCUUCAUUUUCCUCAACUAUUCUACUUUUUUUCAUUUACUCUCUUUUUUUCUUUUCCUCAUCUCCUGUCUCCUAGCAAAAUUAAGACUUUUCUUUCCUUAGUUUGGAAACAUGGAAUUCUGUUUUUGGUGGUUACCUUAGUCUCUGUGUUUUUAGUUUGGAAAUUCACUUAUGCUCAUAAAUACUUGCUAGCAGACAAUAGACAUUAUACUUUCUAUGUGUGGAAAAGAGUUUUUCAAAGAUAUGCAAUUCUGAAAUAUUUGUUAGUUCCAGCCUAUAUAUUUGCUGGUUGGAGUAUAGCUGACUCAUUGAAAUCAAAGCCAAUUUUUUGGAAUUUAAUGUUUUUCAUAUGCUUGUUCAUUGUUAUAGUUCCUCAGAAACUGCUGGAAUUUCGUUACUUCAUUUUACCUUAUGUCAUUUAUAGGCUUAACAUAACUCUGCCUCCCACAUCCAGACUUGUUUGUGAACUGAGUUGCUAUGCAAUUGUUAAUUUCAUAACUUUUUACAUCUUUCUGAACAAGACUUUUCAGUGGCCAAAUAGUCAGGACAUUCAAAGGUUUAUGUGGUAAUAUCAGUGAUAUUUUGAACUGUAAAAAUGGACUUAAUAAUUAGACCAUUUCUACAAAGAACAACUGAAUAGGUGGAAAACAUGGAAUUUCUUUUAGGUGCAGUGGUGGUCCUCAAAUUACAUUAGUUUUUUUAAUAUAUAUUUUAAACAUAUGUAAGAAAUUAAGUGGCAAAGAACUGGGAAAGCUUAAGACCUGCUUCAAAAGCCUGAAUAAUGGGAAAAUAAAAUUGUUUUCAGAUAUCUCAUAUCGCUCUCGUAAUGUUGGCCCCUCACAAAGCUUGGGAAUGUUUUGUAUGUAUAAGUUUAUUAAAACUGGGUAUGCUUCAUAUUACUAGAACUAAUUUAUUCUCUUCAGAGAGAACUAUUAGGUUAGUGCAAAAGUAAUUGUGGUUUUUGCCAUUGAAAGUAAUGGCAAAACCACAAUUACUUUUGUACCAACCUAAUAACAAUGUGUUAGCAAAUAUUUACAAAUGGUCAGGUGAUAUUCUUGACUGAAAAGUUCCUUAACAUUUCAGUAAAUAUAAUUUUAAUUCUAAGUCAAAAUAGAAAUGCAUAGAUAGUAAAUGAUAAAGUAGAGACUCAUAUAUGUCUGUCUAGGCAUCAAAUUGUUGGUUAUUGUUUACAAUCCAGAAAUGAUGAAGCUCUUUCACUAAUUCCUAAUAUGAAAUGUAUGAUGGCCAAAGACAAAUUGUGUUGAUUAUAAUCCUUUAAAAGGGGGAUUUCCUUUAUGAAAUACAUAUUGUAUUAGCUUCCCAGGGCUGCCAUAACAAAUGACCACAAACUUGGGUGCUUACAACAAUUUUCCUCACAGUCUGGAGGCCAGAAGUCUAAAAUCAAAGUGUCAGCAGAGUUGGUUCCUUCUGGAGGCUCUAAGGAAGAAUCCAUUCUAUGUCUGUUUCCUAAUAUCUUGUGGCUGUCUGCAAUUCUUGGAGUUCUUUGGCUUAUGGGCAUAUCUUGUCUAAGUAUUGCAGACAGCAAUCUUCACUCCAGUCUCUGCCUCUGCGUUCACACGGCCUUUCCCUCUGUCUUUUCAUUACCUUUUAAGGACAGUGUCUUUGAAUGUAGGGCCCACCCUGAUCUAGGGUGAUUGUGUCUGGAGACCCUUAAUUAUGUUUACAAAGACCCAUGUUCCAAGUAAGUUUGUAUUCACAUGUUCUGAGUAGACAUUGUCUCUUCAUGGGAUACUUUUCAGUCCAUGACAGUUACUAAAGGACAUUUUAGGAUAAUCCUCAUAUGAUUGUUAGGAGACUACCUUUAAAAAUUUUUUAUUAUAUAUCAAAUUAUAGUUGUAUAUACUUAUGAGGUACGAAGUGGCAUUAUGAUUUUUGAAUAUAAUGUGGGAUGAUUAAAUAAAGCUAAUCUAUCCAUCACCUCAAAUAUUUGACAUAUUUUGUGAUGAAAACAUUUGAAAUGUACUCUCAACAGUAUUGAAAUGUACAUACAGUGCUUAAUUAUUAGCUGUAUUCACCAUGUUGUGUAAUAGAUCUAAAAAAAGUCAAACAUAUUCCUUCUAUCUAAUUGAGGCUUUGUAUCUUUUGAUUGUCAUCUCCCUAUUCCCACAUCCCCGGCCUCUAGCAACCAUCAUUCUUCUCUCUACUUCUGUGAGUUUAAUUGUUUUAGAUUACACAAAUAAGUGAGAUCAUGUGGUAUUUGUCUUUCUGUGCUUGGCUUAUUUCACUUACCAUAAUGUCCUCCACGAUCAUCCAUAUUGUUGCAAAUGACACAAUUUCUUCCUUUUUAAAGGCUGAAUAGUAUUUUUUUGUAUAUAUAUGCCACAUUUUCUUUAUCCAUUCAUCCAUGGAUGGACACUUAGGUUGAUCGAAUCACUUGGUUAUUGUGACUUGUCUGCAAUGAACAUAGAGUGCAGACUUCUCUUUGACAUACGGAUUUCAAAUCUUCUGGAUAAAUAGCCAGAAGUGGGAUUGUUGGAUCAGGAGAUAAUAUCUUAGCUGAUACCUUUUAAAUAACUCUCAGUAUCUUUACUGAGAGGUUAAAAAAUAAGUGACUUCUUAGGUAAUAUAAAGCUAAAGGUGACUAGUGUUUGAUUCCAUUAUCUAUUAAAAAAAGUCAGAAUUGAAAGAAAGUUGAGAAAUCCUUUGGUCUGACUUUGUAGAUUAGGGAACAACUGCUGGGGUAGGAUUAUUUUGUGUUACUUUUUGAAUUUUGUGUUUAUUAUUUUGAGUGUAUUUUUUGGGUUGUCAUUCCAUUACAGGAAAGUAUUAUUUGGGCAUGUUAACUUUGACAUGUAAACUUAGAAUUGUGAAUAGAACUCAUCUUUUAACAUAAUUUUAUGUUUCUAAACUUUAAAAGUAGCUAUAAGUGAACAAAUUACUUUCCCCUCAAUGUCAAAUUUUGCUUCUCUGAGUUUUAAGUGAUGAGUCUACAUUUACAAAUAUAAAAUUGUGUGCAGGUGAAAAUUACAAGUAUAAUUUGAGUAAUAAAUGCAGGCCAUUUUUUGGUUGUACUCUAGUACUCAGAAAAUAGAUCGGCAUUAGUUAUAACAGUGAUUGUAGAAAAACGUGUUUUACCCAGACUUCUUAAAAAUUAGAUGAGAGAGGACACUCAAAGAAAUUAUACUUUUGUCAUUAAUUUACUAUAGUGGAGAACUAAAUCUGGGAAGUCAAAAUUGAAAAAAGAAUGUGUAAUUUAGGGAAAGUAACUUUUUGUCUGAUAAUAUUAAUGCAAGGAUUUUGUAUUUAGGAAUACUUCUGAGAGGAGAAGCUUCCACUCUGAUCUAGUCUGGCAAAAUUGAGGAAAAUAUUCUACCCUGUAAUUAAAGAAGACUGCUCUUUGGAGGGAUCACUGUUCUAUAUCUUUUUUUGUUUGUUUUUGUCUUUGAGGAGAAGUCUCGCUCUUGUCCCCCAGGCUGGAAUGCAAUGGCGCGAUCUUGGCUCACUGAAACCUCCACCUCCUGGGUUCAAGCAGUUCUCCUGCCUCAGCCUCCCGAGUAGCUGAGAUUAUAGGCGCCCACCACCAAGCCUGGCUAAUUUUUUCUAUUUUUAGUAGAGCCGGGGUUUCACCGUGUUAGCCAGGCUGGUCUCGAACUCCUGACCUCAGGUAAUCCACCUGCCUCGCCUCCCAAAGUGCUGGGAUUACAGGCGUGAGCCACUGUGCCCAGCUCUUCUAGUUCAUUUUUAAGUGUUGAGUCCCUGCUGUUUAAGAGAUGUUUUGGUGAAAAUCUACAUUCAGAGAGAAACAGGUUAAUCUUCCACAUUUUUUAUAAAAUACAUAAAAUAUAGUACUUGGCAUUUUAAGAAAAGAAUGCCAUGUAUUAAAAGGUGCUAUUUUCAACUAUUUAUUAUUUUAAAACAGGAAUGCUUAUCAAUACUUUCGAAUUUAAGAUAAAUGUCUUCGUUAAAUUUUCUAGGCAGUUCAAAGAUGGCCAUUUGCUGGUGAAUUUUCCAAAAUAGAUAACAGAUAAAAUGAUUAUGUAAGAACUUGGCACAACAGAUCAUUUUGCCUUUAGUCGUUCAAGAAAUGAUACUAAACUCAAAGUCAUUCACUUGAAACAACUGAGAAGACCAUUCUUAGGUGUUUAGAUCCUUGCUUUUAGAAACAUUCUUAGUUAUAUUUGUGUUUUCAAAAGUUAUUGAGUAGAUAGAUAUUUUUUCAUGAAUUUUUAAACAUUAGACUUAGCUGAAUUGAUUAAAAUUAGGUGAUUAUGAAAAAAAUAUUGCCCUGCUCGAGGGCAUCUGGAGCCCUACAGUUACCAUUACUAAAGUCUGUGAGUAUGUCUAUUUUGAAAAGUGUCAUAAAAAUAUCUAGUCCAUAAAUCAUUAUAGGUUCAGUAAUACAUCAUUUUGAACUGAUUCUAUCUUCUGUGAAAUUCUAGAGAUAUGUUAUCUUUAGGUAGCAUGAGUAAGAUUCAGGUAUGCUGUGAAUUUUGUUAACGUUUAUGUUUUCCAUUAAUGGAUAGUCAGGAAUCUUUUGAACUGCGUCUAUGUAUUUAAAUGAUUUGGAAAGAUAGCAUCUCUCAGUUUAAACUUAGCAUCUCAUUUUGGCAAGAUAAAUUAUUUUAGCUGUCUGGCCUUUUCUUUGUCUUCUUAGAGUUAUUUCUGAAAUGUGCAUAGCCAGUCAUAAAAUAACUUGUGUAAAUAGCCUAAUGUAAUUUAUUUCUAAUAAAUACGUAGCUUAAUGAAAUGUAUUUCUAGUUUGAACUUAAUUGCCACUUGGCUUGAUAUUAUUUUCCUUAGAAUUGUUGGAAGAGAGGAGAGAGGAAGGGAUCUACCAUUUUUAUUUAUACCACCUAAAUAGUGGACUGUUAUUUUGGACUCACUUUUAAAUAAAAUAUUUAUUCACAUGAAGAAAUAAAUUUUGUGUUUAUUAGGUUAGCAAGCGUUUAUUAUCUUUGAAGUAAUUGGAAUUUCAUUAAAAAGUGAAGCAAGUAAGAAUUGUGAUAUAAAUUUGAAAAUUUUUAAAUGGAAAUUGAAAUAUGACUUAGGAACUGUGGGCUUGUAGAAAAAAACAUUUAACAUGGGAGUUAAGAUUUUUAUAUUUGGUUGUGGCUCUGGGAUCAAUAAGGCAAGUGGUUUAGUCUUUAGUCCUCAUUUCAAAUGAGAAUAGUAUUUGUCCUAACUCUAGUCAGUGUCUGAUUGGUAUGUGUAUAACCUUAUUUUAAAAAGGAUUCAUUCCUGCCAUAUACUCAUAAUAUUUAUAAGUAUGUCAUAUGAUAAAUAUUGAGUAAAUAUAUACUGAAUGAAGUUUUUAGUAUAGAGUGAAGUGAAUAGAAAAAACAUCCUACAUAACCGUGGCUAAUUUUAGGAAGUAAAUCAUGUUUCAUAAUAAGAGUCAUCCUAAACAUUUUUCUGUGUAAUUUUCUGACCCAGUGUUAACAAUUUUUAUUUGCCUUAGUGCAAGCUUGUUCAACCCACAGGCCACAUGCAGCCCAGGAUGGCUUUGAAUGCGGCCCCAACACAAAUUUUGUAAGCUUUCUUAAAACAUGAUGAGAUAUUUUGUGAUUUUAUUUUAUUUUAUUUUAUUUAUUAUUUUAUUUUAUUUUAUUUUAUUUUUUAGCUCAUCAGCUAUCAUUAGUGUUCGUGUAUUUUAUGUGUGGCCCAAGAUGGUUCUUCCAGUGUGGCCCAGGGAAGCCAAAAGAUUGGAGACCCCUGCUAGCAUUUAAUGCUUAUACAUGUAUUUACUUGUAAACAUGUUGUUUCUUUGAUAGGAUAUGAUUUCAACAUAAUUACUGUUUAUUUAAAAUAAGAAAAACAAAUAACUUUCAACCAUUAAAAGGUUAUAACACUUUAAAGGAAAGUUUCUUAUUAAAGAAACUUUAUACCCUAUUAAGGGUAUAAUUUCAAAAUAAUUGCUUUUUAUUUAAAAUAAGAAAAUAUUCUUAUUUCUAUUUAAAAUAAGAAAAAUCAGUAACCUUCAACGAAUAACAGGUUAAAGAAUUUAAAGGUAAAAGACAUUUCAACUAAUUACAAAUACUUUGUUUUUUUUAGUUGGGCUACAUUUUACCACUCUAGGAAUAGCUGUUAAUUAUUUUUUAUAUAGGGCAUUUUUAUGUAUUUAAUGUUGACAACUGACGUUUCCAAUAUACAAAAACUUGUGUAACUGAGAAAAUUAUAAUAAAAAUAGAGAUUGAGGACAUAUUUUUAACAUAUAUCCAUGAGUCAACACUAAUAUUUAAUAUUUGAGAUUUGAAAAAUUAUUUCUAGGGUAAGAAAUUCUGUCACAAUAUAAUAUCUCUAUAUUGUGCUUUUUUAAGAGAUAAAUUUUUGAUGAAUUUAAUGUUAAUUAAAUUUUAUCUCAGCCUAUCACCAUCAGACCAAAAGACAAUACAGUAUUUUUCUAACAAGGAAAAGAAAAUACAUAUAUAUAUAUUUAUAUAUACAAAUAUAUACGUAUUUAUAUAUACAAAUUUGUAUAUAUGUAAUGUAUGUGUGUGUGUAUACAUAUAAUUUCUCCUUUUUUUUUUUUGUAAGAAUUGAGACAGGGUGUCACUAUGUUGUGUGGGCUGGUCUCAAAACACCUGCCUCAAGUGAUCCUCCCACCUUGGCCUCCCAAAGUGCUAGGAUUUACAAUGAGCCACUGUGCCAGCUUCCAACAAGAAAAAUAUUAAAUGUAUUGGUUUUUCACAGUGAAACUUAAUUCAGUUUAGUUGAACCAUAUAUGUGUGUGUAUGGCAUAUAUAAGAUGAAAAAAGGAGAAAAAGUAACAAUAAUAAUGAUGGUUGCCAUCAUUCAUUGAACACCUAUAAUGUUUUAGGCAUUAUACUAGCUGAUUUACAAAUAUUGUCUCAUUUGAUGCUACAUUUAUAUUUCUAUGAGGCAGAUGUUGAUUUCUCUUUGACUGCUGAAGAAACUGAAGGUCGGUCAGGUCAGGUGAUUUGCCCAAAGUCCACACUGUCACUAAAUGAACAUAGAUUGGUAUGACUCCCAAGCCUGUGAGUUUUUGACCGUCAUAUUCUGCCUCACUAUGAAAAGUUUUUUUUCAAUUUUUUUUAAAUCAAAAGAAGUAGUAUAUGGAGAGAGAGGUGAAAAUCCAUGUUUGCUCUCUGCAGUUUCCAAACCAUUCAUGACGUGUUAUUUUUGUACUGGAUAUAGUCAUUUUUUAAAAUGCUACAAACUGUUCAAAAGAGCAUGAACAACAUGAUAACUCCUUAUAAUUUUGUUGUAAGAUAAAUGACUAAAAUUAUGUGGGAUAUUUAAUUUGGAUAAGUGGAAAUUCUAUCACUUGAUAAGCUCUCUUGAAGAAUAAUUAUUUGAAAGAUUGGACUUAAUUCUGUAUUGCCUGAAGUGUAAAUCAGAGGUCAACAAUUAGAUUGCAAAUCAUGAAAAGCAUAACUUCUAAUUGUUUAGUCUUUUUAGGGAAACAAGCCCAGAAAAAAAGUAAGAUUCUCAUUCAUUGGAGAUAAGAUUUCUAUUUAUCAAAGAUACUACACAAGAGUUAGAUAGCAAGUAGUUCAAAUGUCUUUUAAAGGUAUCUGACAUCUUUAAAGCUCUGUAAUUUUUAAAUUCUAAAUUUUGUUACAGCUAAUUUUUAAAAAUUAAUUGCUAAGUCAUGGUCAAGUAUUUCUGAUGACUUACAUGCUGUCUUUGGUAUAUUUUAAGUUUCUAAACCAAAACUACUAUUUGACUCUAUUACACCCUGUUUUAGAAAAACAUUUGAGUUAUACAACUUACUAAAAUGUAUUUUAGCGGUGAUGUUUUGGAGCACUGGUAAUAUAGUGUUUAACUUAUUUUCUAUUUUUUAUCCCUCUAUAUUCGUGAAAUUACUUCUAUUUGAAAAGUUUUCCGCCAGUGAUAAAAAAAGGCUGAGCACUAUCUGUAAAAAUUUUUAAGGUGUCCACUAGGUGGAGAUAUUGUGCUACAUUUCCAAGUGUUGUAGUUAAACUUUUAUUAGUCUGAAUUAAACUCUUUUAUAGUGUUUUAUUGUUUUAAACCACAAAGAUUUAUAAUCAUUUAUAUCUAUUUAUCUAAUGUUAUUCAAAUGUUUUCUGCGUUGUAUGAAGCUAAGAUAAAUGUAAAAAAAACAAACAAAAAAAACCUCACUUUGUGUUUUGUAAUCAUUAGACGAUUUAACCUAAUAUAUCUUCCCAUAUGAUAUGAUCUUUGCAUAUGGCAUACUUCAUUCAUAUGACAUAGUUAGAAUCUUUUCCCACAAACAAUGAGUGAUGAUAUCUCAUUUGAAAACUCGUGUAACAUUGUAUCAGCCACUGUUAUAAAGUGAUUUACCCAUGUUAGUCUCAUAACAACUCUAUGAGAUCAGUACCGUACACAUGGGGAAACUUAGUAUAGAGAGGUGAAGUAUUUUUUCCAAGAUUACAAAAUAACUGUCUGAGCUGGGAUUCGUAACCAGGCAGCCUGACUCCAAAAUCAAUAUUCUUAACUCUAUUGUUAUGAUGGAGAAAGGCAUGAAGUCUACCUUCAAAUUCAUGGCAUUUUAGAAGGAAAAAUUGUCGCAAGUAAUGUGAUUAUACUUCCUAGUUUUAUAGGUCAGAAAAAUGAGGUCCACACUAAUUUUGCCUCUUCCACAGGGAGAUAGAUUCUCAUCUACCAUUGUGUCUUUUGUUUCUGUUUUUGUCAUGAUACCUCAAAUUGAUAUAUGUUGUAAUUAUGAAUUUAAGGAAGUAAAAAAAUAACUCAGGGCUGGAGCCUUCAGCCAUAUUAACAUACAUUGACAUAAAGACCUUUGUUUUAAUAUGAAUGAUUCCAGUUAACAAAUGGAGAAAUAGUUGUUUGAAAAUUAAUAUUUAGCUUCUCAAAAGAGACUCCUGUUUGGAAGCAAAUUGUUGGUUUAACAGGACAUACUUUAGAUAUUUGAAAAAUUCUCUGUGGAAUCACAAUCUCUUAUUUUUAAGAAUGUAGGAAUAUGUGUUCUAUAUGCUUUUAAGUUAUGUAUUACAUACUAUUCUCUAAAAUAGAAAUGUUUAUUUGGCUUCUAAAAGUCAUUUGUGAGUUGAUGUUAUUUAAAACUGCUUUUCAGUCAACUUAUUCUUUAUAAAAAAGUUUGUUCAAAUAGCAUGUUUUUAUUUUGUUUCUAAAUAAAUUCAUGUUUGAUAAUA